GCUCUUUGCAGCCGCCGCCGCCGCCGCAGCCUCCCCCUCGGCGCAGGGGGAACUUUUCUACUCUCUGUGACGGUCUCCCCCGCCGCCCCCGGGGGCAAGCCCAGCUGGUCCGCCCGCCCCGCCCGCGGUCGUGCUCCCAGCCCGAGCCUCUGCGCCUCGGGAAGUUUAUUCUGCCCGCCCUCCUCCCCUUCCUCCUCCUCUUCACCCCGCCUCCCCGCCCUCCCCCGGCUCUUUCCCCCGGGUGGCUGCCGCUGCCGCCGCUGCCGCUGCCAGCCUGCUCCUCGGCCAGCCGCGCCGGCCCCAGGGCCGGGAAGCUCCCGGCCCCACGCACCGCUCCGCUGCAGCCACCGCAGCCGCCGCCGCUCUGGGCCGGCCCUCGGCCCCCGGCUCCCGGCCCCGCAGAGUUCCGGGCUCCCUCGCCGGCUGCACCGCCCCGCCCCGCCCCGCGCCGCCCCGCGCCGCGCCGACCUGCAGCGCCCGGCUGCCUCGCACUCCGCCUCCCCCGGCUCAGCCCCCGGCCGCGGCGGGACCCGAGCCUGGAGCAUUGGUAAGCGUCACACUGCCAAAGUGAGAGCUGCUGGAGAACUCAUAAUCCCAGGAACGCCUCUUCUACUCUCCGAGUACCCCAGUGACCAGAGUGAGAGAAGCUCUGAACGAGGGCACGCGGCUUGAAGGACUGUGGGCAGAUGUGACCAAGAGCCUGCAUUAAGUUGUACAAUGGUAGAUGGAGUGAUGAUUCUUCCUGUGCUUAUCAUGAUUGCUCUCCCCUCCCCUAGUAUGGAAGAUGAGAAGCCCAAGGUCAACCCCAAACUCUACAUGUGUGUGUGUGAAGGUCUCUCCUGCGGUAAUGAGGACCACUGUGAAGGCCAGCAGUGCUUUUCCUCACUGAGCAUCAACGAUGGCUUCCACGUCUACCAGAAAGGCUGCUUCCAGGUUUAUGAGCAGGGAAAGAUGACCUGUAAGACCCCGCCGUCCCCUGGCCAAGCCGUGGAGUGCUGCCAAGGGGACUGGUGUAACAGGAACAUCACGGCCCAGCUGCCCACUAAAGGAAAAUCCUUCCCUGGAACACAGAAUUUCCACUUGGAGGUUGGCCUCAUUAUUCUCUCUGUAGUGUUCGCAGUAUGUCUUUUAGCCUGCCUGCUGGGAGUUGCUCUCCGAAAAUUUAAAAGGCGCAACCAAGAACGCCUCAAUCCCCGAGACGUGGAGUAUGGCACUAUCGAAGGGCUCAUCACCACCAAUGUUGGAGACAGCACUUUAGCAGAUUUAUUGGAUCAUUCGUGUACAUCAGGAAGUGGCUCUGGUCUUCCUUUUCUGGUACAAAGAACAGUGGCUCGCCAGAUUACACUGUUGGAGUGUGUCGGGAAAGGCAGGUAUGGUGAGGUGUGGAGGGGCAGCUGGCAAGGGGAGAAUGUUGCCGUGAAGAUCUUCUCCUCCCGUGAUGAGAAGUCAUGGUUCAGGGAAACGGAAUUGUACAACACUGUGAUGCUGAGGCAUGAAAAUAUCUUAGGUUUCAUUGCUUCAGACAUGACAUCAAGACACUCCAGUACCCAGCUGUGGUUAAUUACACAUUAUCAUGAAAUGGGAUCGUUGUACGACUAUCUUCAGCUUACUACUCUGGAUACAGUUAGCUGCCUUCGAAUAGUGCUGUCCAUAGCUAGUGGUCUUGCACAUUUGCACAUAGAGAUAUUUGGGACCCAAGGGAAACCAGCCAUUGCCCAUCGAGAUUUAAAGAGCAAAAAUAUUCUGGUUAAGAAGAAUGGACAGUGUUGCAUAGCAGAUUUGGGCCUGGCAGUCAUGCAUUCCCAGAGCACCAAUCAGCUUGAUGUGGGGAACAAUCCCCGUGUGGGCACCAAGCGCUACAUGGCCCCCGAAGUUCUAGAUGAAACCAUCCAGGUGGAUUGUUUCGAUUCUUAUAAAAGGGUCGAUAUUUGGGCCUUUGGACUUGUUUUGUGGGAAGUGGCCAGGCGGAUGGUGAGCAAUGGUAUAGUGGAGGAUUACAAGCCACCGUUCUACGAUGUGGUUCCCAAUGACCCAAGUUUUGAAGAUAUGAGGAAGGUAGUCUGUGUGGAUCAACAAAGGCCAAACAUACCCAACAGAUGGUUCUCAGACCCGACAUUAACCUCUCUGGCCAAGCUAAUGAAAGAAUGCUGGUAUCAAAAUCCAUCCGCAAGACUCACAGCACUGCGUAUCAAAAAGACUUUGACCAAAAUUGAUAAUUCCCUCGACAAAUUGAAAACUGACUGUUGACAUUUUCAUAGUGUCAAGAAGGAAGAUUUGACGUUGUUGUCAUUGUCCAGCUGGGACCUAAUGCUGGCCUGACUGGUUGUCAGAAUGGAAUCCAUCUGUCUCCCUCCCCAAAUGGCUGCUUUGACAAGGCAGACGUCGUACCCAGCCAUGUGUUGGGGAGACAUCAAAACCACCCUAACCUCGCUCGAUGACUGUGAACUGGGCAUUUCACGAACUGUUCACACUGCAGAGACUAAUGUUGGACAGACACUGUUGCAAAGGUAGGGACUGGAGGAACACAGAGAAAUCCUAAAAGAGAUCUGGGCAUUAAGUCAGUGGCUUUGCAUAGCUUUCACAAGUCUCCUAGACACUCCCCACGGGAAACUCAAGGAGGUGGUGAAUUUUUAAUCAGCAAUAUUGCCUGUGCUUCUCUUCUUUAUUGCACUAGGAAUUCUUUGCAUUCCUUACUUGCACUGUUACUCUUAAUUUUAAAGACCCAACUUGCCAAAAUGUUGGCUGCGUACUCCACUGGUCUGUCUUUGGAUAAUAGGAAUUCAAUUUGGCAAAACAAAAUGUAAUGUCAGACUUUGCUGCAUUUUACACAUGUGCUGAUGUUUACAAUGAUGCCGAACAUUAGGAAUUGUUUAUACACAACUUUGCAAAUUAUUUAUUACUUGUGCACUUAGUAGUUUUUACAAAACUGCUUUGUGCAUAUGUUAAAGCUUAUUUUUAUGUGGUCUUAUGAUUUUAUUACAGAAAUGUUUUUAACACUAUACUCUAAAAUGGACAUUUUCUUUUAUUAUCAGUUAAAAUCACAUUUUAAGUGCUUCACAUUUGUAUGUGUGUAGACUGUAACUUUUUUUCAGUUCAUAUGCAGAACGUAUUUAGCCAUUACCCACGUGACACCACCGAAUAUAUUACUGAUUUAGAAGCAAAGAUUUCAGUAGAAUUUUAGUCCUGAACGCUACGGGGAAAAUGCAUUUUCUUCAGAAUUAUCCAUUACGUGCAUUUAAACUCUGCCAGAAAAAAAUAACUAUUUUGUUUUAAUCUACUUUUUGUAUUUAGUAGUUAUUUGUAUAAAUUAAAUAAACUGUUUUCAAGUCAAA